GUUAUAUACUCCCAGCCUUUCUGAUUCCAUUGUAACUCUUGCCGAAAUCCGGGUGAACGGAAGUAGUCUCUUUAAGAACUGGUAUGGGCAGGCCCAAGUUGUCAAGGCUUCGGAGGUAAUGCCCUGGAGAGCGGGGAACGGGGUGGGUUUAGAGGCCCAGGCGGGCACCCAGGAGGCAGGCCCAGAAGAGUACUGCCAGGAAGAGUUGGGCGCCGAGGAGGAGAUGGCAGCCAGAGCAGCAUGGCCUGUGCUGCGCUCUGUGAACUCACGCGAGCUCUCCCGGAUCAUCAUCUGCAAUCACAGCCCACGAAUCGUGCUGCCUGUGUGGCUCAACUACUAUGGCAAGCUGCUGCCCUACCUGACGCUGCUGCCCGGCAGGGACUUCCGCAUCCACAACUUCCGAAGCCACCCUUGGCUCUUCAGAGAUGCAAGGACACAUGAUAAGCUUCUGGUUAACCAAACUGAAUUGUUUGUGCCAUCUUCCAAUGUUAAUGGACAGCCUGUUUUUGCCAACAUCACACUGCAGUGUAUACCCUGAAAGAGCAAUGCCUCCAGGUUGUCGGAAGCCUAGUCAAGCCCAAGAAUUACAGGAGACUGGACAUCGUCAGAUCACUCUAUGACGAUCUGGAAGAUCAUCCAAAUGUGAUUGAAAGACCUGGAGCGGCUGACGCAGGAGCACAGUGA